GAGUCAGAGCCUCUUCUCUCUAAGUCACGGGAACUGCCCUUGCUACUUGUGACCUGCCCUUUACUCAGCAGUUUUUGUUCUGGGAAGCCCUGGGAUUCUGCUAAUACCUAUCACUGUAGGUGCUGAAGGGAAACAGAUGAAGAACAUGACCUCAAGGAGCUUCCUGUCAAUGAGAAGACCAAGCUGACGCCUGGCAAAGAUAUUAAAGAGGAGCCUGAAACUGUUCCUUGGACAUCUUAUGAAUGUCAGAAAAUACCUUUUGGAGGGUUAGAAGAUCAGGGGACAUGGUUGUUCACAUUUGCUGCCACGGAACACCGCCAGUCUUCACUUGGAAACAGAAUCACGCCUUGUGAAGAGAUCAUCCCUAAGCAGGAGAGAAGCUACUAAAGGAUUGUGUCCUCCUCCACCUUCCCUGUGCUCGGUCUCCACCUGUCUCCCAUUCUGUGACGAUGGUUCAAUGGAAGAGACUCUGCCAGCUGCAUUACUUGUGGGCUCUGGGCUGCUAUAUGCUGCUGGCCACUGUGGCUCUGAAACUUUCUUUCAGGUUGAAGUGUGACUCUGACCACUUGGGUCUGGAGUCCAGGGAAUCUCAAAGCCAGUACUGUAGGAAUAUCUUGUAUAAUUUCCUGAAACUUCCAGCAAAGAGGUCUAUCAACUGUUCAGGGGUCACCCGAGGGGACCAAGAGGCAGUGCUUCAGGCUAUUCUGAAUAACCUGGAGGUCAAGAAGAAGCGAGAGCCUUUCACAGACACCCACUACCUCUCCCUCACCAGAGACUGUGAGCACUUCAAGGCUGAAAGGAAGUUCAUACAGUUCCCACUGAGCAAAGAAGAGGUGGAGUUCCCUAUUGCAUACUCUAUGGUGAUUCAUGAGAAGAUUGAAAACUUUGAAAGGCUACUGCGAGCUGUGUAUGCCCCUCAGAACAUAUACUGUGUCCAUGUGGAUGAGAAGUCCCCAGAAACUUUCAAAGAGGCGGUCAAAGCAAUUAUUUCUUGCUUCCCAAAUGUCUUCAUAGCCAGUAAGCUGGUUCGGGUGGUUUAUGCCUCCUGGUCCAGGGUGCAAGCUGACCUCAACUGCAUGGAAGACUUGCUCCAGAGCUCAGUGCCGUGGAAAUACUUCCUGAAUACAUGUGGGACGGACUUUCCUAUAAAGAGCAAUGCAGAGAUGGUCCAGGCUCUCAAGAUGUUGAAUGGGAGGAAUAGCAUGGAGUCAGAGGUACCUCCUAAGCACAAAGAAACCCGCUGGAAAUAUCACUUUGAGGUAGUGAGAGACACAUUACACCUAACCAACAAGAAGAAGGAUCCUCCCCCUUAUAAUUUAACUAUGUUUACAGGGAAUGCGUACAUUGUGGCUUCCCGAGAUUUCGUCCAACAUGUUUUGAAGAACCCUAAAUCCCAACAACUGAUUGAAUGGGUAAAAGACACUUAUAGCCCAGAUGAACACCUCUGGGCCACCCUUCAGCGUGCACGGUGGAUGCCUGGCUCUGUUCCCAACCACCCCAAGUACGACAUCUCAGACAUGACUUCUAUUGCCAGGCUGGUCAAGUGGCAGGGUCAUGAGGGAGACAUCGAUAAGGGUGCUCCUUAUGCUCCCUGCUCUGGAAUCCACCAGCGGGCUAUCUGCGUUUAUGGGGCUGGGGACUUGAAUUGGAUGCUUCAAAACCAUCACCUGUUGGCCAACAAGUUUGACCCAAAGGUAGAUGAUAAUGCUCUUCAGUGCUUAGAAGAAUACCUACGUUAUAAGGCCAUCUAUGGGACUGAACUUUGAGACACACUAUGAGAGCGUUGCUACCUGUGGGGCAAGAGCAUGUACAAACAUGCUCAGAACUUGCUGGGACAGUGUGGGUGGGAGACCAGGGCUUUGCAAUUCGUGGCAUCCUUUAGGAUAAGAGGGCUGCUAUUAGAGUGUGGGUAAGUAGAUCUUUUGCCUUGCAAAUUGCUGCCUGGGUGAAUGCUGCUUGUUCUCUCACCCCUAACCCUAGUAGUUCCUCCACUAACUUUCUCACUAAGUGAGAAUGAGAACUGCUGUGAUAGGGAGAGUGAAGGAGGGAUAUGUGGUAGAGCACUUGAUUUCAGUUGAAUGCCUGCUGGUAGCUUUUCCAUUCUGUGGAGCUGCCGUUCCUAAUAAUUCCAGGUUUGGUAGCGUGGAGGAGAACUUUGAUGGAAAGAGAACCUUCCCUUCUGUACUGUUAACUUAAAAAUAAAUAGCUCCUGAUUCAAAGUAUUACCUCUACUUUUUGCCUAGUAUGCCAGAAAUAAUAUAAAUAUAAACAGAUAAAGUGUGUGAGACUUUUUCUCAUAACUAUUCAUGACAUUUAAAAUCCCUAGGGGCUGGCAAGAGAGUUCUCAUUAUUCUGAAAUGGUCCUGACAAGCUGCAUGAAUAGCAAUUUUUUUUUUGAGACAGAGUCUUGCUCUGUCACCCAGGCUGGACUGCAGUAGUGCAAUCUCAGUUCACUGCAACCUCCGCCUCCCAGGUUCAAGCGAUACUCCCACCUCAGCCUCCUGAGUAGCUGGGACUACAGGCAUGCAGCACCAUGUCUGGCUAAUUUUUGUAUUUUUAGUAGAGGCCGGGUUUCACCAUAUUCGCCAGGCUGGUCUUGAACUCCUGACCUUGUGAUCUGCCCGCCUCGGCCUUCCGAAAUGCUGGGAUUACAGGUGGGAACUACUGCGCCUGGCCUACAAAUAGCAAAUUCUAACGAAGACAGGGGAACAGGGAUGGUUCUUCCAUUGUUAAAAGCCAUCCUCAUUUUGUUUAUAUUGCCAGGUUUGUGAUUUUUCUGUAAAGGAAAAGGCAGGGUGAUUUAACCAGUUUGACCACCUUUCCUGUACUCUUACAGGAAAAUCGCAGCACUAAUUCUAAUUUUGUCCACUUUACAGCCAAAGCUUAGCUAAUGUUCCAUAAAGGAGAUAAUAGCCAAUCAGGUAAGGUAAUGUGUAAUUCAUUAUUCAAAGUGGAACAUGUUUUUGUAGGGGGAGAGUCUGCACUAUUAAUAAUUGUAUUGAGAAAUAAAAAUAAACUAGGACUAUUCAGUUAAACCAGGAUGUCUUAUUAUUCCAUGUUUAGGCCUCUUGAGUCAAAACUCUUUUUUUUUUUUUUUUUUUUUUUUUUUUUGGAGACAGGUUCUCACUCUGUUGCCCAGGCUGGAGUGCAGUGGCAUGAUCUUGGCUCACUGAAGCCUCUGCCUCCCAGGUUCAAGUGAUUCUCCCCCCAAACCUUGCAAGUAGCUGGGAUUACAGAUGUGAGCCACCAUGCCCAGCUGAUUUUUGUGUAUUUUUAGUAAAGAUGGGGUUUCACCAUGUUGGCCAGGUUGGUCUCAAACUCCUGGCCUCAAGUGAUCCACCUGCCCCAGCCUCCCAAAGUGCUGGGAUUACAGGUGUGAGCCACCAUGCCUGGUCCCCUCUUGAGUCAAAACUCUUAUUUCAGAAUGCGAAUGGAAGGAUCGCUAUUAGUGAUUCUGCAGAUUACACAUUUCCUUGCGGGGAGACAAUAAGGUAUGUGUAAAUACAUAUAUGUGUGUGUAUGUAUACACACAUACAGCACGCUACCUCCCAAGUGUUACCUAGUGAAACAGUUUCCUUUCCGAAGCUCCAGAGAUGGUUGUUGGCUAAGUUAUACUCUUCUGUGAUGGGCAAGGGAUACUAUAAAAACAUAGGCAGUGCCCUUUGAAUAUAGUACAGCUCAUCUUCUGCAUACGAUAUGCCCUGGAAAGGUGAUUUAUAUGCAAGUUAAUUGGUGUAAUCUGAAGGAUGCUCCCAUUAAUACGUCAUGAUGUCAUUAAUAUGUUUCUUCCUUUCUGAUUUUUGUUUUUUUUUUUUUUUUUGAGACAGAGUCUCACUCUGUCACCCAGGUUGGAGUGCAACGAAUGGCGCAAUCUUGGCUCAUUACAACCUCCGCCUCCUGGGUCCAAGCGAUUCUCCUGCCUCAGCCUCCUGAGUAACUGGGAUUACAGGUGUGUGCCACCUUGCCUGGCUAAUUUUUUUGUAUUUUUUUAGUAGAAACAGGGUUUCACCAUGUUGGUCAGGCUGGUCUGAACUCCUGACCUCAAGUGAUCCACUUGCCUUGGCUUCCCAAAGUGCUGGGAUUACAGGCGUGAGCUACCGCACCCAGCCCUUUCUGAGUGUUGUCAUUCAAUUCAUCAAGUUUUCUGUCAUGAUCAACUUUCUCUAUGCAAACCCUGUAACUCUGACAGUUAUCACUGUGUCUGACACAGUGAAUUUUUUAUUUAUAAGGUAGUUACUUUUGGCCAGGUGUGGUGGCUGACGCCUGUAAUCCCAGCACUUUGGGAGGCCAAGGUAGGCAGAUCACUUGAGGUCAGGAGUUCAAGAUCAGCCUGGCCAACAUGGUGAAUCCCCAUCUCUACUAAAAAUAUAAAAAUUAGCCAGACAUGGUGGUGGGUACCUGUAAUCCCAGCUACUUGGGAGGCUGAGGCAGGAGAAUCGCUUGAACAUGGGAGGCAGAGGUUGCAGUGAGCUGAGAUCGUACCACUGCACUCCAGCCUGGGCGAUAGAGCCAGACUGAGUCUCAAAAAAAAAAAAAAAGUUACCUUUUUUUGGUAAGGUUGUACUUCUUAGAUAAUGGUCAUUGUCACUACCAACUUGCCUGCAUUGUAAUAGAGUCCUAUUCACUUUGCUCCCAACCCCACUACGGAGAUGACUGAUGACUAGUUGUAUACACAGUGGGUGUGCCCUGAGAGGUCUGUUGCCAGCAGUGGUGAUCGAUCACGGCCUCCCCCUGCUGGCUGAUGUGAUGGUCCUUGGUCCUCCUCUGAAGGAGGUAGAAGGGGCACACGGCCACCGUGGGAAGUAGGCAGAAAAGCCUCCCUGGGUGCAGAUUCUCUGAGAAAAGAACUUUGGCCUCAUAGUUAACUUACUCCAAAAGCUUUCAUGUGAAAUAAUUUAUAAUUUUUUAUAUAAAUAAAAAGAUUAAAAUGUGAA